AUUUUGGGUGGAAGCGAUAGCUGAGUGGCGGCGGCUGCUGAUUGUGUUCUAGGGGACGGAGUAGGGGAAGACGUUUGCUCUCCCGGAACAGCCUAUCUCAUUCCUUUCUUUCGAUUACCCGUGGCGCGGAGAGUCAGGGCGGCGGCUGCGGCAGCAAGGGCGGCGGUGGCGGCGGCGGCAGCUGCAGUGACAUGUCCAGCAUGAAUCCCGAAUAUGAUUAUUUAUUCAAGUUACUUCUGAUUGGCGACUCAGGGGUUGGAAAGUCUUGCCUUCUUCUUAGGUUUGCAGAUGAUACAUAUACAGAAAGCUACAUCAGCACAAUUGGUGUGGAUUUCAAAAUAAGAACUAUAGAGUUAGACGGGAAAACAAUCAAGCUUCAAAUAUGGGACACAGCAGGCCAGGAAAGAUUUCGAACAAUCACCUCCAGUUAUUACAGAGGAGCCCAUGGCAUCAUAGUUGUGUAUGAUGUGACAGAUCAGGAGUCCUUCAAUAAUGUUAAACAGUGGCUGCAGGAAAUAGAUCGUUAUGCCAGUGAAAAUGUCAACAAAUUGUUGGUAGGGAACAAAUGUGAUCUGACCACAAAGAAAGUAGUAGACUACACAACAGCGAAGGAAUUUGCUGAUUCCCUUGGAAUUCCGUUUUUGGAAACCAGUGCUAAGAAUGCAACGAAUGUAGAACAGUCUUUCAUGACGAUGGCAGCUGAGAUUAAAAAGCGAAUGGGUCCCGGAGCAACAGCUGGUGGUGCUGAGAAGUCCAAUGUUAAAAUUCAGAGCACUCCAGUCAAGCAGUCAGGUGGAGGUUGCUGCUAAAAUUUGCCUCCAUCCUUUUCUCACAGCAAUGAAUUUGCAAUCUGAACCCAAGUGAAAAAACAAAAUUGCCUGAAUUGUACUGUAUGUAGCUGCACUACAACAGAUUCUUACCGUCUCCACAAAGGUCAGAGAUUGUAAAUGGUCAAUACUGACUUUUUUUUUAUUCCCUUGACUCAAGACAGCUAACUUCAUUUUCAGAACUGUUUUAAACCUUUGUGUGCUGGUUUAUAAAAUAAUGUGUGUAAUCCUUGUUGCUUUCCUGAUACCAGACUGUUUCCCGUGGUUGGUUAGAAUAUAUUUUGUUUUGAUGUUUAUAUUGGCAUGUUUAGAUGUCAGGUUUAGUCUUCUGAAGAUGAAGUUCAGCCAUUUUGUAUCAAACAGCACAAGCAGUGUCUGUCACUUUCCAUGCAUAAAGUUUAGUGAGAUGUUAUAUGUAAGAUCUGAUUUGCUAGUUCUUCCUUGUAGAGUUAUAAAUGGAAAGAUUACACUAUCUGAUUAAUAGUUUCUUCAUACUCUGCAUAUAAUUUGUGGCUGCAGAAUAUUGUAAUUUGUUGCACACUAUGUAACAAAACAACUGAAGAUAUGUUUAAUAAAUAUUGUACUUAUUGGAAGUAAUAUCAAACUGUAUGGUGAUAAGUAUUGUUUUGAUUCUUAUGGUUAAAGGGAAAUAGAGCCUUGCAUUAUAUUCAACACAGCCAUUUGUGUGUGCACAAUGCAAACUAAGGUAUUCUAGACCUAUCUUAGAGCAGCAUCCAGUAUUUGCUUUCUAGAUAAUAUGCCCAAUAACAUGACCUAGAGGGGCUUCUGUGCUGUGUAGGGAUUUAACCAACUUCAGUGGUUCAGGGAGCUCAAACUAUAUGUAAAACAAGUUUAGAAUGUAUGCUAUCUAGCCCGUUAUCUCUGAUCCUUCUCUAAAACCAUUUGAAAUAGCUUCAUUGAUCAACAUUUCAUAAAUGCAUCUGUGGUAGAGGUAGAAAGCAGCACCUUUCCUAAUUGGCAAAUGAUCAGACUAAUGUGUGCUAAUGUUUUUCUUCCAUGCUUUCAGUCAGAUUCAACUAUUUUAUCCUCCACAGUUGCUUAACUUGGUGUUGGAGGAGGGUUUAAGCAUUAAGAUAGGAAGCAGGAAAUUUGAUUGCUCUAAAUUUAGAAAUUAUAUCCCUAAAAAUUAAAACAUGAAUACUGGGUGGUAAUGAUAAUUGAGGCAAAUGUAUUUAUUUUGGUGACAUUUUGCAUAUAUGAAGAUUUUCUGAAAUAGGACCUUCAAGAUCCUAGGGGGUUUUGUUUGGUUUUUAAUUGUGAGGAAUAAAAAAUCUUCUGCCCACACUGGCAUUUUAAGGUGACUGAGGUCAAACGUUGUUUCCUUAGGUUGAAAUAGCAGCCAAAACAUUCUUCACGCAGGGGCUUGGGAUAUGGCUGCUGGCAACACAUUUUGUUGUGGGCUCCUUAAUUUAAUGAUAAAAUUUAAGCUAAACACAAGCCAAAAAUGAAUAGGUUUUUUUAAUUUUUAUUUUUCACUAAACAGGCAAUUGAAAUACAUGGUACAAAAAUAAGUGGUAAGAUAAUUGUAAAAUGAAAUGGACAGAAUAUUCAAUUUUCCAUCUAUGAAAAUUUCACAAUAAAAAUCAUAGUUUACUUUGUA